CUUGGUAGGAGUUAAAUGCCAGUAUAUGUUUAUAUUACCUUAAUUUGUUUUCUUUAUCUAUAAAUAAAUCUUGCCUACUUCUGUUUGCAGGGUAAAAUUAAGGUGAUUUUCUUCUACAACAUGAUUGAGCUAGCAUACUCUCCAGGAGGGAACAGACAGGCAUUCUGAAAGGAUGUUUGGUAUUUUUAGAGCCUUUUAUACAUUUGUUUCUGCUGUUGUGCUAAUAUGCUAAUGUUUAUCAAGGUUGUAUUUUUUUCCCUCCCUUUUCUUUCUUGCUGCUGGCAGAGCAGCAUUAUAGAGUUAUGCAGCAAACUCUCCUUUGGGCAUUUGUCAUUACUACAAAGUGUUUUACAUUUCUUUGCUCCUUAAAAUAUAUGCUGCUUUUCUGCUGAACCUAGGAUAAAAAGAACAAGGCAGUAUCUUUGCGAAUCUUAAUUCUUUCGAGUUAGGGAAACCGAUCCAGCAACCUCUCUUUCACACCUUCCCAUUUUCCCAGUGAACCUCAUAUUCGGUACAGCUCUGUACCUUCCUGCAGUGAAAUCUAUAAACCAGAGCCUCCUGCUUCUUUUGCCCCAGUUGACUUCAAGGCUCAGGGCCCAUGGUUGUGCACUGGGAGAUAAUACACCAGCACUGCCUAGUUAAAGGGCACAGGCUCCUCAGUCAGACAUACCUGUAUUUGAAAUAUGGCUUUGCCUCCAACCAGCUGUGUCACCCUGAGCAGGCACUUAGUUACUCUGAACCUUCUUUUGCUUAUCUGUAAAAUGAGCUUCUGCUGGUAUCUUCCUUUAAUUGGAGAAUCUCACGAGGUAAUGCUUUCCAAGUGGAAUAACACAGUUUCUGGAAUUUCAUGGGACUCAGAAAUGUUCACUAGUAUUUGAUUUGGAUCAGCAACGUAAGACUUUGCCAAGGCACCCCAAGAAGAAUGAAUUCUAAAAUAGCAACCUGCUGUGAUCCAGUUUCUGGAUAAUCUGAAAGCUCAACUGUCAAUUCUUUUUUGGAAGUACAGAUGAUUUUAUUAUUAUUAUUUUAAACUGAUGCUGCUUGCUUUACUGCUAGAGGCCUUAGAUAAGACAUGUGGCACUAUCAGAGAUGCGUUGUCAAUGGAACAAAAAUGGUCUCGGACGCUGGUCUGAUCCUAGUCUGAUGUCCUGUGAAGAAUAACUCAAGUGUUGUUUCUCUUGAUGCGGGAACUUUAAAGUACUUUUCUUCUCUAGCUAUCCACUCUAAUUAAGUUUUACAUCCCUUCAACGCUGGCUUUUCAGGUACCAUAUCGUCAUUAUUAUUAUUACCAAUUUGUCAGCUGCUUUAUUUGUUCAUACUUUAAAAUGGAAAACAGUAAUUUUAGGUCAGGAAUGGCAGUAUAGUUUUUGUCUGUGGUGGUUCCAAGUAGUUUUUAAUUGACACAGGAUUUACAGACUGACUAAAAAGAGAAAAAGUCAGAUGUGAUAAUAGAAAGCUCAUGGGUUUUUUUUAGGCAGGGGGACCUGGAUUCAAAUCGUGACUCUCUCUUAAUCAGCUGAGUGGCCUUAGACAAGCUACUUAACCAACCUGUCUCACCUUCAGACUUCUUCUGUGAGAUGGGGAUAACCUAGUUCAAAUGAGAUGAAAAGUAAAUUUACUUAUAGUAAGUAGCACAUUUUUUCUUUUUGAGACAGAGUUUUGUUCUGUUGCCAGGCUGGAGUGCAAUGGCGAGAUCUCGGCUCACUGCAACCUCCGCCUCUGGGGUUCAAGCAAUUUUCCUGUCCCCGCCUCCCUGUAGCUGGGACUACAGGCACGCACCACCACACCCAGCUAAUUUUUGUAUUCUUAGUAGAGACGGGCUUUCACCAUGUUGGCCAGGAUGGUCUCAAUCUCUUGACCUUGUGAUCUACCCACCUUGGCCUCCCAAAAUGCUUGUAUUACAGGUGUGAGCCACUGCGCCUGGCCCUAAGUAGCACAUUUUAAGAUGCUUUCUGAAUGUGAGAUUUUUCUAGUUCUUCCUUUUGCAAAUUACUGUUCUUUUUCUGUGAUUGUUGAGUGAUUCAAGUAUAGAAAUUCCAUGAUUAGAGUUUAAAAAUAUCUCUACAAAUGUAUUUAAAACAAUGAGCAGGGCUCAGUGGGCACUAUUAAAACAAAAUUAUUUAUAUGAUCACCUACUAUUUUUAUCUUAAUGAUUGCCAGGUAUCUACUUGUUACACCUUUCCUCCUCUUUUAUAUUUCUGGAUUAAAUAAUAAUAGCUAACUUUUUUUGAGUACUUGUCAUGGGCACUGUUCCAGUUUAUUUGCAUAUAUUAACUCAUUUAAUCUUUACAACAGCCUUUGAAGAUGGGCCUGUUAGUAUCCUCUAUUUUAUAAAUGAGGAAGUGAAACUCAUGUCAGCUGCCAUUUCUGCCAUCCAUAGGUGUGCAAAACAGGGAGAACCCAAGUGGAGAGUGGUGAAGAGUAUUGCAGUGCUAAACAAAAGUGACGUUCUGUUUUCAAAGGUGACUUCCAAUGAAGACUACUCUUUAGCCUGAACAUGGAGGGAAAAAGAACAGUGUCAGUACCCACAGUCCUAUUCUUCCUUCUACAUCUGACAUUAUUAUUUUUUUCCUUUCCAUAGGCUUAGGCUUCUAAUCCCGAUGAUUACUUUUCUUACCUAUUUCUGUAGCAUGUUUUCAUGCUGAAAGAGAAGUUGACGUGCUGUUGUCAUCGUAUUAAGGCCUAAGCAGAACAGCAUUAUUGGUAUUAUUAUUUUUCCUCUCACAAACAGGAUUCCACUUAAUCUCUUUUACCGGAUGGCACAGUUAAAGUGCCUUCUUCAUCAGAGCCUGUUUUAAACAAGCAGGCCUUUUAUUUUAUGACACUUAUAUUGAGACACAUUGAGUUAUAUCUGUCUUUUCAUUUGCACCAACACAUUUAUUUGAGGCCUCAUAUUUCCUAGGUAACGUGACUAAGGUAGAUUUAUCGGUGCUAAUUUGCAUACAGAACAACAUUGGCAAAACUAAAAUAUAACAAACACAUACUAACUUUUGACUUGCCACAGCCCACCAAGCAUCUGCCUUCAUUGCCAUGCCUGUAAUGAGAGGGAAAUAUAUUUUCCUCUGAGUUUAAAUCUAAUUCCUUGUUUGUAUUCCACUGUCGUCACUGCUGUUGAGAGCUCGAAGUGAGGUUUAAGAGCCUCUUCAUAUCUAACAGCAGGAGUUUAUAUUAGAGGUGGUAGUUCUGUAUAACAGAAAAUGCGGCUUUUGCUCACCCACCUCGAUUUCAUACCACAUUUGAAGAACCCUGCUACAUUUAAGUAAGGGGCAAGCCCUUUGUUUUGCACAAAAGUUAAUAGAGACUUAAGGCUACACCAUUGUGUUAAAGCCUGGCUUUUAUUUCUUUUUCUCAAUGUUGCUUUUAAGUAGAUUGAUAUUUAUGGCACAAAUAAUAAAUGAAUUUAUUUAAAAAUUCAUUAUUAAAAAAAUUUUUUUAAAUUAUAGAUUAGGUUGAAAUUUCUUGGUCUGCCCUUCCCAAGUUUACUGGCAAUAGCUUGGUGAACAUCAUCUGGACCUUUUCCUAUACAUUUACUUAUGCAUGUAUCUGUCCUUAGAAGAUACACAUUAUUGCUUCAUGUGUGAACAUGUGUGUCUAAUAUAUGUUCUUCUGCUGUAUGUAUUGUUCUGCAGCUUGCUGGUUUCUUUUAGUCUUGUGCCUUGUAGAAUAAUUAGUGCUACCAUGUUCAGACUUAAUAGGCUAGAUUAGUCAAUGCUGUUAUCAUGAGUUAUUCCUAAGAUCUCAGUGGUUAACACGUCAAACGUUUAUUUCUCAGUCAUGCACAUGUGGGUCAGGUGACAUCCCCCAUGUUGUAACUCUUAUAAUCCAGCCUAAUCUCACCUGUGAUUCCACCAUCUCCACAUGUGGCUUCCAGGUCCUUGUAGCCAACAAAUAGGGCUCUGGAGGGUUGCACAUGGUCUCUUAAAAGUUUUGGCAUACUAGCUACAAGAGAACUGAGAAAUGUAGGGGUACACAUGGUUACUUGGUGAUACUGUGUUGCCAUAGAUAAUGUUAAAUAGUUCACACAGUCAGAAUAUAUUAUAGUUUGUUUUGCCAGUCUUCUAUUUGAUGGGCAUUUGGAUCAUUUCCAAUCGUAUCCUUUUGUUAUGUACAAUUCUCCAGAGAAGAUCCUUGCAUGUAUCUCUGGUACAUGUUUUGCUAGGAUAGAUACCCAGGAAGUAGACUUUCCAGGUCAGAGAAUGGGGGUGCUUUAGUUUUCAUAAACACUGUCAAAUUGUUUUGGAAGGUGGUUGCACUAGUGUUCUGUUGUAAGGAUAGUAUCUGAGAAAGUGCAUUUCACCUGACCUUCAACAACAAUAGCAUCAGAUCUCGUGUGUGUGUGUGUGUGUGUGUGUGUGUGUUUGUGUUUGUGUUUGUGUUCAGUGGCAUCUUCAUUCCUUUUGGCAAAAUGGCUUCUUCCGUUUUGUUUGAGUUUCUAUUUUCUUGAUUACUAGUAAGUCCUGGGCUCUUUCUAAUACUGCUUUAUGCUGCCUUCCCAAGUGAGCAGUACUAGUGUGCAAAGUCGAGCUGAAGAAGGCUGGAGCAAGUGCAGAGCCAGUGGGUAGACGAUUUUCCCUUUCAGGGGUGUCGAGCUCAGGGACAUUUCUUUUGAUAUUCUCUGUUGAUUCCCCCACCUCCCCACCCCAGGUGCUAUUUCAGUUGUUUCUACACCUCUAAUUUUAAAACCAUGGGGCGAAGGAUGAUUUCUUGGGCAUGUCAUUUUUUUUUUUCUGUGUAGCUGUCUGGUUUUGUGCUUGGAGUUUUUAUGUCAGUUUUUGCCCACUUAGCCAUUGUCUUGUUAUCUUCUGGUUCUCUUUGUCCCCUGCCUCAUUUUUCAUUCUUUUUCUUCUGCUUCUGCUCCCUUGUUCCCAUAGGCCCUUAAAUCUUUAUGUGUUGCUUUUCUUUUAAGUUGUAUUUUUCCCCUUCCCCUCCAAGCUUAGAAAUGUUUGCUCUAUCAAAGAAACGCAGGAAGGAAGGGAAUGAUGGCAAGGAUAUUGUACAAGUCCAAAGGGAACAAAACCUAGGUGCCCACCUACCCCAGCUAGUUUAAGAAUGUGAUGCUGUUCCUAUCACGGUCACUUUGCCAAAAUCCAUGUGAAGGAAGGAAAAAAGCUGGGAAUUAGUCCAGCUUUCAUCAGGCCUCUGGCUUACUAUAUGAUCCCUAGGCAAGACACUUUCCCUCAUCAGGCCUCCAGGUUCCUGACUGUAAACUGAGGUGAUUGGACCCCAGUGGUCCCUUUAUAUCUUGAAACCCCAGUAUUUGAAACAUGUGACUAACUGGGAAACUUCUCCAGUAUAGGGUCCCAAAGACCUUUUUAAAAGUGGAUCACUGCCAUUCCCCUUCACCUUCAGCCUGUGAAGCACUGUGUCAGUAAGGGCCAGUCAGGAAGACAGGGAUUUUGUGAGGUCAUUUAAUAGAAUUUAACAAAGGGCCGGAAAGAUUGUAAGGCACACAGGCUUGGGAGGCAACACAGAGAUGGAUGGACAACAGCAGGAAUCUUCCGUGAGCCAUAGGAGAGGAAGGAAAUGGUGUUGGCCGAGUCUAGGGCUAGCUGUUACAAGCAGAAGUCACAGCAGGGGAGAUAGCAGGAGCUGGAAUGUGGAAGAGAGGGCUGUCUGGAGAGACCUGGAGCUUCAGAGGAGAUGCUGUUACACCCACAAAGAGGACAACAAAGCCUGGUGUCUUCCCCCUACUGUUCAGUCUCUGAACAGAGUCUCAAAUUUAGGCAGAAGAGCCUGUGGAAUGGUCCUGAGGGCAGGCUGGCAAAUGACUGGCAGAAACAAUCAAAAGGCACUGGGGCAGAUGAUCUUUAUACUCCAUUCCAUUCCUUGCAUUCUAGAAUUCAUGGAUUAUCUGAGAGAUUCUUCAUGUCUCCUGCAGCAAAGAUGUUAUUUUUAGGGUCAUAACAGGUAGCUCUUCCUAGGAGUUGAAAUAAACUUCUACCAUUCUAGCAUCUUAGGACAACACCUAUUCACAUCUCCACCUCCCUCCCUCCCAAAGCCUGGAGUAGUUACAUUUUACCUUACACGAGCUCUGUCAGCAUUUCGUGAAAGUCCUAUUCCUGGUAGACUUUUGACGAAAGGGACACUAUUUUACUUGUCUCUUAUCUCAGUCUCUAUCACCACAGAGCCUCUGGGACCAGAAUACAAACACAGGGAACCAAUAGUGUUACCCAGUUGAUCCAGAAGUUUUACUGUUUCAGAGUAACUUGUGAUCUUGGGCAAGUUCAGCCCGUUUCCUAAUUUGUAACAUGGCUUUAUUGGUCAGUAAAGCCAAUUGGGCAAAAAGGUUGUGCAAUAGUAACAAAUAACCCCCAGAAUUUCAGUGGCUAAGAAUCCACAAAGGUGUAUUUUUUACUACACAUUUACGUAAAGUCACUUGGUAUAUGUCCAUCCUUAUUCUGGUCCCUGGCUGAUAGAUCAGCUACCAUCUUGAAUGUUGCCAUUCCCCAUAUCUAGAGAGGGCAAACUUCGAUGGGGUAGGAGGGAUGGCAAUUAAACGUUGGCCUGAAUGUGUCACACAACAUAUGUACUCACAACUUACUGGCUGGAACUAGUUAAUUGAUAUGAUACUGUGAUAUAAUAAAAAAAAUACAUAUUUGGUCUUUACCCCUGGUUCCUGGCACACAGUUCCUAAGACCCUUGGGAUAUCUGAAGUGAUGAGUGUCUUUUCUACCCUAAUGAGAUGACUAGUGGUUGGAGUCCACUAGGUAGCUUCAGGAUUGUGACUGGUUACUAGAAAGCCCAUAGCAUAAUUAGAGGGUUGGGACUUUCGGUUCCAUCCUCCCAGUCUCUGGGGAAGAGAGCGGGACUAAAAGUUGAGUUAAUCGCCAAUGGCUAAUGAGGUAACAAUCAUGCCUAUGUAAUAAAAUAAUAAAAUCUUAAGAGGACAAGGUUUGGAGAGUGUCCAGAUUGCCAAAUAUGUGGCGGUAUCUGCAAGGUGGUACCCCCAGAGAGGGCAUGGAAGCUCCAUGGGCAUACCUUGUUAUGUACACCUCUUCCAUCUGGCUGUUCACCAGUGUCUUUUGUCAUAUCCUUUAUAAAUAACUGGUAAAUGUCAGCAGUGGUUUUUGUGAGCUCUGUUAGCCAUCUUAUAAAAUUAGUUAAACCCGAGGAGGAGGUCUUGGGAACUCCCAAUUGAUAACUGGUUGGUCAGAAGCACAGGUAAAAUAACCUGGGGCUUGUGCCUGGCAUCUCAAGUGGGUAUAGUCCUGUGGGACUGAGCCUCUAACCUGGGGGAUCUGGUGCUAACUCUAGGUAGUAGAUACGGCAUCGCCUAACUUCAGCUGAAGUAAGGAAGUGCCUAGAAGGAAGAAGACCGAGGAUAUUUCUUGAUUUGCACUAAUGACAGCUACAGAGAGAGAUAAUAAUUCUUGACAUUUCCUGAUUGUUUUAACCAUGAAACAUGAAUAUUUAAUAUAAUGCCUAGCUCAUAAGUGCUCAAUUAAUAGUAGAUGGAACUAUUAUUGUUAUUAUUAUUCAGCAGUUUAUAUUACAUUUCCAGCGUACUUUCUACCAUCCAUUUGCAUAGCAGAUUUCUUCUCACCCUUUUUUUACAACUGAGAAUGCAGAAGUAAACAUAAAUUAUACUUCUGUAGAUGUAUCACAUUUUUUUUUGUUUUUUGAGACUGAGUCUCACUCUGGCACCCAAGCUGGAGUGCAGUGGCACAAUCAUAGCUCACUGCAGCCUCAGCCUUCCAGGCUCAAGUUGUCCUCCAGCCUCAGCCACCCAAUUAGCUGGUACUGUGGGCAUGCACUACCACAUCCAGCUAAUGUUUUCACUUUCUGUAGAGGCAGGGUCUCACUAUGUUGCCCAGGCUAGUCUUGAACUACUGGGCUCAAGCAAUCCUCCUGCCUCCGCCUCUCAAGAUGUUGGGAUUACAGGUGUGAACCACUGCGCCUGCCCACACCCAGCUACAAAUUCUUAAUAAGUGGAGUUGUCUUGAAGUUUUAGAGCCAGUCAGGGCCCUAGUUUUCCAAGUUUUGGAUUGACAAAAAUAGGUGAUUAUUCUGUAAAAGAAUUCCUUUGUGGAGUGAUAGCCGGGUGUCAUCAGUGGAUUUGGAACUGUGCUCAUUGUCCUGGUUUUCAAUUUAAGAGCAACAGACUUCAAGCUGGCUUUCAUUUGAGUCAGUGUGGAAACAGUCAAUAUAUGUUACAUGUCUGUGAAGCUGGCCUCUGGAUCAAUUGCAAUUAGUUUCCAGCAGAUUGCAUUAACAUAUCUAAAAUUAAUAUGGCGAGUGUUCUGAUGAAAAGGAAUUGACCACAACCACAUUGUGGCUGUUUUUAGUCUCCCUCAAAUGCUCUUUUCAAACUAUAUUUUUUCUUUCUUUGGUUAAUGGCUUUAAAUUGUUAUGUCAACGUAGACAUAAUCUAUUGAUUGUUCCUAUUUGCCUUUUAAGAGUGGUCCUAGAUAAUAGCACACAGCUAAUGUUUAAUGUUUUCUUUCACUAAGGGGCUUUUUCGCUAAAUGCCUUAAACUCGUAUUUUUCUUUGUAUGUUAUAUAACACGCUAUUAAGACUAUAAAGCCUUUGAGUAUGUUCAUUUACAGAAUUUUGUGUUUUUCAAAUUACUAAUGUUUCAUCAAGACUUAAAAAGUAAGAUUAAGAAAUAAUGUGUAGUUAAAAAAUAAUAUACGGUAAAUGAUGUGAGCAUUGCUUGUCUGACAAUUUAUUUUUAUCCCAGUAUUAUUUAUUUCUAAAGAAGAAGUAUAGGCAACUUCAAUAUUAAAAGCAAAACCAAACCAUCAUUACCAGCAGCUACAAGGACGGAACAGAGAGCUAUCUUUAGGCUUGAUCAUGUUGAAAUUUGAAUUUUUUACCAGCAUGUAUACAUUAUAUUAUGUUUAUUUCACAUCUUAAGGACUAACUUGUACUUUUUUAUUUUUAGAGGUGGCCAGUUUCUGGGAAUGAAAAAUUGUCCAUAUCAGGAGACAAAAGGCAGAGUUGAUUCAUUUGGCCAUCCAAGUGGCAUUUUUUGGGUGUCUUUCAUAUGUCAAGCACUGUCACCUUCUUCACAGAGAUACAGAGAAGUUUAAGGCACACUUUCUACCCUUUAGUGGAACACAGUCUAGUAGUGGGGGUAUAGAGCUUUGAAUCACCCUAUUUCAAAAGAGCUCCAUGAAUACAUCAUAGCUUGGGGAUACCAGAAGAAAAUGACAUUUUAAGGACACAGUAGAUGUCCCAAAAGGUAAUGGCUCCAUGUGAUGAAGCCCUGUGGGCCUCACUUUUAUGAUCUGUGUGACACUGCCUUGGACAUCCACCAAAGCCGUGGACAGAAGCCAGUAGGGAUUGUAUCAGAUGAUGUCCAUGUACUACCAGUCUUGUGAUCCAGUUGUGUGAUUGAUUUUUUUGGUUUGUGCAUUAACUGUAUUGUCAUCCUUCCUCUUGUGAGUAAUGUUUCCUUUGCAUAUGACUCAUGGAUGGAAAGGAGUUUACAUUAAGUGUAUUCAUUUUUCCUGGUUUUUUUUUUUUUUCCUUCUUUUAAAAAUGGGGCUUACAGAUUUGGUAGGGAAUACUGUUGAUAUUAUUGGAUAAAAUGUAAGGAAUUUAUUUGUUCAUGUUAUUGUGUCCUUUGACUGUGUCCUUUUAACACAGAUAAACACGUAGUGCAUAUUGGAAAACCACUUCUACUUGAAACUUAAGCAAAUUUCCUUUAAUACACAAGUUGCAGUUUAGGAACUAGUUUAAUUAAUAGUCAGUCUUUCAGGUUAUUGCACUCAACCUUGGUGGAUGAAAGAGAUAAUCUCGUUAAACACACAAUGGCCCUACCCAGACUCUGUUAAAAACUGUGGUAAAGAAAUGAAUUAGUCUGUGGCCCAGUGACUUCAGAGUGUUUAAACAAAUUUCCUGAAAAACCUUACAAUGAUUAACAGUCUAUAUACAGUUAUUAAAAUAAUGCUAUGCUCUUUAUUUAUUUGGGGUGAGAAGGGGGGAGCCAUAUCCAUGUAAUAGAGUCCUUAACAGUUUUUAAAAUAACUUAUGUUGAAAUACUUGUAGACUCAAAGGAAGUUGCAAAAAUAGUAUAGCAGCCCCAUGUACUCUUCAUCCAGCUUCCCCUAAUGCUGACACCUCAUGUAGUUGUGGUACAAUAUCAAAAGCAAGACAUUGAUAUUUGUGUAUUACUGUUAACUAGAUCACAGAGCUCACUCAGCUUUCAGCAUUUUUAAAAAACCUGCAUUCAUUUGUGUGUGUGUAGUUGUCCUUAACAGUUUUUGUUAAAAAAUAAUUAGGCAUGAAUUUAAGUGGGUUUUUUUUUUCUUUUGCUUCUCUCAACUCUGGGUUGCAGAUUGCCAGUCAACAGUACCUCUAAGACUGGCCAUGUAGGUUGACUUUUAUUUUUCUUGCUAUUAAUGAAUGUUCUUACCUCUCUCCUUCAAUUUCUGUAGGCAGUUCAAUUAACCUCCAGAAGAUGGCUGAACCUGCAGGAAUACCAGAGCAAGAAACUGAUGUCUGACAACGGAGUGAGAGUUCAAAGAUUCUUUGUAGCAGACACUGCAAAUGAAGCUCUCGAGGCUGCUAAGAGACUAAAUGCAAAAGAAAUUGUUUUAAAAGCCCAGAUCUUAGCUGGAGGAAGAGGAAAAGGUGUCUUCAAUAGUGGUUUGAAAGGAGGUGUUCAUUUAACAAAAGACCCUAAUGUUGUGGGACAGCUGGCUAAACAGAUGAUUGGGUACAAUCUAGCGACAAAACAAACUCCAAAAGAAGGUGUGAAAGUUAACAAGGUGAUGGUUGCUGAAGCCUUGGAUAUUUCCAGAGAAACCUACCUGGCAAUUCUGAUGGACCGGUCCUGCAAUGGCCCCGUGCUGGUGGGCAGCCCCCAGGGGGGCGUCGACAUUGAAGAGGUGGCUGCUUCAAACCCGGAGCUCAUUUUUAAGGAGCAAAUUGACAUUUUUGAAGGAAUAAAGGACAGCCAAGCUCAGCGGAUGGCCGAAAAUCUAGGCUUCGUUGGGCCUUUGAAAAGCCAGGCUGCAGAUCAAAUUACGAAGCUGUAUAAUCUCUUCCUGAAAAUUGAUGCUACUCAGGUGGAAGUGAAUCCCUUUGGUGAAACUCCAGAAGGACAAGUUGUCUGUUUUGAUGCCAAGAUAAACUUUGAUGACAACGCAGAAUUCCGACAAAAAGACAUAUUUGCUAUGGACGACAAAUCAGAGAAUGAGCCCAUUGAAAAUGAAGCUGCCAAAUAUGAUCUAAAAUACAUAGGACUAGAUGGGAACAUUGCCUGCUUUGUGAAUGGUGCUGGGCUCGCCAUGGCUACUUGUGAUAUCAUUUUCCUUAAUGGUGGGAAGCCAGCCAACUUCUUGGAUCUUGGAGGUGGUGUAAAGGAAGCUCAAGUAUAUCAAGCAUUCAAAUUGCUCACAGCUGAUCCUAAGGUUGAAGCCAUCCUUGUCAAUAUAUUUGGUGGUAUCGUCAACUGUGCCAUCAUUGCCAAUGGGAUCACCAAAGCCUGCCGGGAGCUAGAACUCAAGGUGCCCCUGGUGGUCCGGCUUGAAGGAACCAACGUCCAAGAGGCCCAGAAGAUACUCAACAACAGCGGACUCCCCAUUACUUCAGCCAUUGACCUGGAGGAUGCAGCCAAGAAGGCUGUGGCCAGUGUGGCCAAGAAGUGAUGUCUUUGUCCUGAUCCAAUGGAGAAAGAAAGCCAUUUUUCCGUAAAAAGGGAUGGUUCAUCAUUGUGAAAGAAAUGGUUAUCUCAUUGGGGAAGAAAAGGGGAGGGGGAAGGCAAGAAUCACUGAAAAAUCUUAAAUCUGUGUUUUCUGGAAUAAGAUAUCUAGACAGCCUAAAUCUGAUUUUGGUCUUUAUAAAAAUAAUAUCUUGUGUUCUCAUACUUUUCUGUCACUGUAAGCCUGCCCAGUAGGCAGUGUUUUGCAGACUUUGGGGAGUGGUCUAUGUGGCCAAAUAUUGUGUGUAUAGACAGAAUUUGAAAUCAAGUCCUGCUUCAUUUACAAGAAUUUUGGUGGGCAUCUAAUCCUACAUAAUGAAAAAGAAAAACAGACCAUUUAAAAACUCAGACAAGAUUAUAUUUAAUAUAUUAAUUACUAAAAAGGCAUAAGAUUACACUGAACAUAUUAGCUACUAAAAAGGCACUGCUAAGACAUUCAAGCAAAUAGCUAUUACACACUACUGCAGAUUUUACAGGUUUCUAAUUCUAACAUAUGUUUGAAAAAUCCGUGAGUAUUCCAAAAUAUAUUUAAUAAUGGAAUAUCUGCAUUAAUAUACCAUCCAUGUGUUUUUACCAUUUGCCUUAAUAUUGAAUAUACUGUUUACCUCACACUAAAAAGAAAACCAGAAGCCUUAUUUGUGAUUUUGGGAGUGGAAGCUUCCAUUUUUGUGUCAAAAAUGAAUCCUGAUUCUUAUGGAAAUCUCUGUUAUUAAGAUAUUUCAAGAUGAGACAACACUGAAGAUCAAAUUGUGUUUAGUAUCACUAUCUUCUCUCCUCGUUUCUCUCUUACUCCUCAUCCUCCCAGAAUCUACCAGUUUAUGGUAGAAAGAUGGGAACCUUAUUUGAAUGUGUUUUUUUUUUCCAUGAUGUCCAAUUUUGUUGUGGGAAAGGAUUUGGAUAAAAUUUUUGUUUAAAUUUUGGUAGAUUUUUAUCUAUACAAAUUUAAAUAAAAUUAUGUUUUGUAAGCUGUAA